ACUUCCCGACAGGACUUCCCACCAGCCCAGCCUUUCAGUGCAGGCUCCAGCCCUCCACCCCCACCCGAGUUGCAGGAUGUCGAUGACAGACUUGCUGAACGCUGAGGACAUCAAGAAGGCGGUGGGAGCCUUUAGCGCUACCGACUCCUUCGACCACAAAAAGUUCUUCCAAAUGGUCGGCCUGAAGAAAAAGAGUGCGGAUGAUGUGAAGAAGGUGUUUCACAUGCUGGACAAGGACAAAAGUGGCUUCAUCGAGGAGGAUGAGCUGGGAUUCAUCCUAAAAGGCUUCUCCCCAGAUGCCAGAGACCUGUCUGCUAAAGAAACCAAGAUGCUGAUGGCUGCUGGAGACAAAGAUGGGGACGGCAAAAUUGGGGUUGACGAAUUCUCCACUCUGGUGGCUGAAAGCUAAGAAGCACUGACUGCCCCUGGUCUUCCACCUCUCUGCCCUGAACACCCAAUCUCGGCCCCUCUCGCCACCCUCCUGCAUUUCUGUUCAGUUCGUUUAUGUUAUUUUUUACUCCCCCAUCCCCUGUGGCCCUCUAAUGACACCAUUCUUCUGGAAAAUGCUGGAGAAGCAAUAAAGGUUGUACCAGUCA